ACUGGUGCUGAACCCCGCCGCGCGCGCUUUGAAUUUCCCAGCCGCUAAGCGCCUCUCCUGGUCGGUGUCCCAGGCAGAAAGGUGCAGAGACCCAUCUGACGCAGGACUCCAGGUAGACAAGCUCCAGCAGAGAGUGGCCAGAUGUGGUGCCUGGAGCGACUCCGCUUGGGUCCUGAGUGCCUUCGGCGGAGCGGAGACUGGCUUCUCCCGGGUCGGGCCCGCGGAGCCAAGUCUCGCACCACCGCCGCGUGCGCAAAUGUGCUCACUCCGGACCGCAUCCCUGAGUUCUGCAUCCCGCCACGGCUCAUGCCCCGCCUGGCCUUGGCUGCGCUCCGGAAUUCUUGGGUCGAAGAAGCAGGGAUGGACGAGGGCGCCGGCCGCACAGACUGGGACCCGCGCUCGCAGGCCGCGCUGUCACUGCCGCACCUGCCCCGUGUGCGCACCGCCUACGGCUUCUGCGCGCUGCUCGAGAGCCCGCACACGCGCCGCAAGGAGUCGCUCCUGCUCGGGGGCCCGCCCGCGCCCCGGCCCCGGGCCCACACCUACGGCGGCGGCGGCGGCCCGGACGCCCUCCUGGGGACCCUGCGCGUCCCGCGAGCUCCGGGCCCGGCGACCCCCGCGGCCCCCGGCUGUCCCCGCCCGCCCCAGGACGCGCUCGCCCGGCGGCCCCGCGGCUGCCGCCUCCUGCGCGUCCCCGACGGGCUGCUGAGUCGCGCGCUGCGGGCUGGGAGGAGUCGCCGCCUGACCCGCGUCCGCUCCGUCUCCAGCGGGAACGAGGACAAGGAGCGCCGCGCGGGCUCCCAGUCCCCGGCCCGGGCCCCCUCCACGAGCCCGCCGUCGUCCCGGGUCCCGUUUCCCGAGCGCCUGGAGGCCGAGGGCACCGUGGCUCUGGGCCGCGCCGGCGACGCCCUGCGCCUGGCCGCCGAGUACUGUCCGGGAACCGGGCGGCUCCGCCUCCGGCUGCUCCGCGCCGAGAGCCCGGCCGGAGGCGCCCCCGGGCCCCGAGCCGUCAGCUGUCGCCUCAGCCUCGUCCUGCGGCCGCCGGGCACCGCGCUUCGGCAAUGCAGCACUGUGGUGGGGCGCAGCCGCAAGGCCUCCUUUGACCAGGACUUCUGCUUCGACGGCCUCUCGGAGGACGAAGUGCGCCGCCUGGCCGUUCGAGUCAAGGCCCGGGACGAGGGCCGCGGCCGGGAGCGGGGCCGCCUGCUGGGCCAGGGUGAGCUGUCCCUGGGCGCCCUCCUGCUGCUCUGAGGGCCCAGCCCUCCCCGGGGCGCUCUGCCCGGGGGACUCCGGACACUGACAGCCGCGUGGUACAAAAUAAACGUGUAUUUGUUGUUCUUAUCAGUCCCGUUUCAGUACAACACUGGCAGAGAUGAUUCUAGAUUAACUAUCCCAGUAAAAGAUAUGAUAUUUUCCAUAGAUACCUCCAGAAUUUUUUUCAGCAAAUGGAAUGGUUCUACAGUGUUUCCCAAUAUAGACAGCCAUUUGCAUACCAUAUGUACCACACACGCCUAGGAAAUAAUGAAUCACAUGAAGUGUUAGAACUAGAAAGUGUCUUGGCGAUCUGUUUGCUCCAAUCACCUCAUUUUAAAAUUGGUGCUUUCCACAACAUGCAUGGAGACCAUCUUGGAGCAUUUACUUUUGAAGCAUUUUGUUUAAGACCCCGGAUAAGAAAAUGAGGGCAAAAGAGGUGAAGUGACUUGUCCAAGAUCAACAGUGAAUUAUUAGUUGGAACGCCAGCCUGAUACUCCUAGCUAUAUCUCACUGGAAAAGCAUUGGAGAAAAUGAAACCAUUUUAAUAUUCUAAGCUUAAAUAAUAGUUAUAAUAGGCUAGGUGUGGCGGCUCACGCCUGUAAUCCUGGCACUUUGGGAGGCCGAGGCGGGCAGAUGGCUUGAGCCCAGGAAUUUGAGACCAGGCUGGGCAACAUGGGAAGACCGCGUCUCCAUAAAAAAUACAAAAUUUAGCCGGACGUGGUGGCACGCACCUGUAGUUCCAGCUACUCUGGGGCUGAGGCGCAAGGAUCACUUGAGCCUGGGAGGUCAAGGCUGCAGUGAGCCGAGAUCGUGCCACUGCACUCCAACCUGGGCAACCGGAGUGAGACCCUGUCUGCAAAUAAUAAUAAUAAUAAUAAAUAGUUUUACAAGCGUUAAUUUAUGUUUUAACCCCCAAAAGGAGGCACUGCUAUGCCCAUUUUACAGAUGAGGAUAUUGAGGCACAGAAUAAAGAGCAGAGCCAGAAUUUGAACCUAGACAAUCAGCAUUUCACUCAUUACUCUUAUGUAGGUAAUACCACAGUGUCUAAAGGGCUCGCUAUUAAAGUUGCGAGUAUUGUGCAACUUCUCUCUGAAACUGUUGACACUGAAGUUCGUGUCUACUUGUAUUCCUCAUCCUGCUUUUGGUGAAAAAACAAAUUGCUUGAAAUGAAUAAUUUAUUAUCUCAUGCUAAUAACUUCAGGCAUUGAGAUGAGCUGAUGGGUCUAAAGCUCUGAGGAGGAAGCUAACCGGCCUCAGAAUCAUAGAAAUGGGUGCCAGCCUUGUUGUAACCAGGUGAGUUUAUCUGCUGGAACAGGCAGUGGAGAGUGUACAGAUAGCAUGGUUUUACCUCUGGCUUCUGAUAAUAAUUCCAGAUUUAACAAUCCUGUUUUAGAGGACGAUUUUCCCUCAUCCCUUGAAUUCACUGCCAGCAGGGCAUUUUUUUCUUUUUUUUAUGCAAAUAGGAAAAUGCAUCCUAAAUGAGGGUUUAAAAAAUUGAAAAUAUUUAAAUAUACAGGAUGGUGUUAAAUAUGACUCCAUUAUCAAUCUGGAUUCAGAAAUGGUUUCUGCUUUAUUUUAUUUCAUUUUAUCUUUUAGAAACAAGGCGUCACUCUGUCACCCAGGCUGGAGUGCAGUGGUGUGAUCAUAGCUCACUGCAGCCUCUACCUCCUGACACAAGCUGUCAUCCCGCUUUGGCUUCUCAAAGUGCUAGGAUUAUAGGCGUGAGCCACCAUGCCCGACCAGUUUCUGCUUUUAUUAAAAUUGUUCACAGUUUUAUACAUUCAUGUUCAUUAAAAAUGCUAUUUAGAAAAGAGUUUGAUAAAAUAAAUAUUAUACAAAAUUCGAAGAAAAAAGAAAAGAGUUUCUGUUUCAGUCACAAAUUAGGGUUAUUGUGAUGUGUAUUUAUGAUGACCAUUGAACAAAUGUGAAGAAUACUGUGAAUUCUAUGACUUUAUCAAAAUCAGCCACAUCCAGGAGCUUGCAGUUGUUGACCAAAUGAAUGAUGACAUAGAGUAGUUCAGAUCUAUCAUGUGCUCUUCUAUCUAAUCAGUCAAUAUUUCCUUGGCCCUCAAGCCAACAUUCAUUUUUUAUGUAUAACCUUCUUCAUGAUUUUGAAAUUUUGAUAGGGUAACUGCUAAUGAGUUCACAAAUGUAGCACUUUAAAAGGAAAAUAAAUGGAGAGUGAAAACAA